AGCGCUGCAGCCUCGGGAGACGCCGGCCGGGCCGGGCCCAGCGUCGCAGGGCUGCUGGCUGCGGGGCAUGCUCACCCCAGGAGUGGUGAAUGUGGGAGCUCGCGGCCACCUGCAUCACCUGUCCCGCCCCGACGCCGUGGCCAGCCCUGCGACAAGGCUGGACUGGGCGGGGGGCUGAGGUGGGCACCGGGCUGCCGCUGGCUCCCACACUGCCCGCUGUGCCCGCUGCCCCAGCCACCCCUGCUGCCGGAGCCUCCUACCUGGGCCGCAACGGCCAGGAUCGCAAAGAAAUCCCUCCCCUCGGUGCAGCUGCGGGCACACAGCAUCUCCCUCUCAUCAGCACUGUUGAAAGAAGAAAAAAUGUCAGUGCUAUCUCCUGAAAUCAAAUGUGAGACUUCUAAAUUCACCAGAAGUUCCUUUGGCAGUUGUUUGAUUUUUGAGAGUAGUUGGAAGAAAGCAGUUUUAGAAACACAAAAGAUUAAGAAAGAAUAUACCACAGCAUUUGGUCUAGAAGAGCUCAAGGAAUGUAUCAAAAUGCCAUAUUUACCAGGACUGCAAAGUUGCCAAAAAAGUGUAAGUUCAACUCCACUAGAGGUUCCUAAAAGACUGCCACGUGCUGAUGCCGAGGUGUCUGCAGUCAGGCUAAAGAAGACUAAGGAGACAUGCAGUGUGGCACCACUUUGGGAGAAAUCAAAAGGUUCUGGCUUCAGUGAUCCUCUCACUGGAGCACCAUCUCAAUACUUAGAGAGACUUUCCAAAAUAGCCAUAUUGGAAUAUGAUACCAUUCGUCAGGAAACAACCACAAAAUCAAAAAAAAGCAAGAAACGAGACCUCCGAGACCGCUGAAAAAUGUCGUACAGUGUGAUGCUUUCUUCAGUGACUUUUAAGCUUUAUAUUUUCUUUUUUUAUAUGAUAUGAUGCAAAAUGAUUUAUAUAAAAAUGGAAAUGUAAAUAAAUAAAUAUUUUACAUUA